AGUGACUUCCAGUCUUCUCUGAAAGAUCUCCACGAUGCUGGCAGCCCGGACAGGGGCAGCGGGGAGUCAGAUCUCAGAGGAGAACACCAAGUUAAGGAGACAGUCUGGGUUUUCUGUAGCAGGGAAAGACAAAUCUCCCAAGAAAGCCUCAGAAAACGCUAAAGACAGCAGCCUUAGUCCCUCAGGGGAAAGCCAGCUCAGGGCGCGUCAACUGGCUCUGCUGCGCGAAGUGGAGAUGAACUGGUACCUAAAGCUCUGCGACCUGUCCAGCGAGCACACCACCGUCUGCACCACAGGCAUGCCGCACAGGAAUCUUGGAAAAUCAGGACUCAGAGUUUCUUGCUUGGGUCUUGGAACAUGGGUGACAUUUGGAGGUCAAAUUUCAGAUGAGGUUGCUGAACGGCUGAUGACCAUCGCCUAUGAAAGUGGUGUUAACCUCUUUGAUACUGCCGAAGUCUAUGCUGCUGGAAAGGCUGAAGUGAUUCUGGGGAGCAUCAUCAAGAAGAAAGGCUGGAGGAGGUCCAGUCUGGUCAUAACAACCAAACUCUACUGGGGUGGAAAAGCUGAAACAGAAAGAGGGCUGUCAAGAAAGCAUAUUAUUGAAGGAUUGAAGGGCUCCCUCCAGAGGCUGCAGCUCGAGUAUGUGGAUGUGGUCUUUGCAAAUCGACCGGACAGUAACACUCCCAUGGAAGAACUUGCUAGGAUGUUUGAGACAGAAGAUAGUUUGAGAGGCUGAGGAUGAAUUAAAAAGAAUGUUCCAGUUAACUGAAGUUUAAAAUCAUAUGGAUUAUCACUUACCUGAGGUGAUUGAGAAUGAAGAUAUUUGAGAAAAAGAGCAAAAAUGAAUAUUCUGGUUAUUUGAACAGUAUGAUGUGGAUUACCACUUUUAAAAUAAUUAGAAUAGUUUGAUUCACAUGAGAUUACAUUGAAGGUAACUUUGUCCUUGAUGAUUCAAAAGGCAGGAUCUUGUAAUAAAUCAGGCUCUGUAAAGAGUGGUUCUUGUUAUAGGGUUAUAGAAGGGUUAUAGUAAUGGAAAAGUAUAAAUGAUUGACAUAUUAUAAAUUUUUCUGGGUUGUAUUUCUGACCAUAAAAAAGUUAUGGAAAUUAUUUUCCUUGCCAUUUGUCUCAUUCUCAACUACAGAGAAAUGUAAAAUAUAUAUAGUCUUAUAACUAACUUUCUCCUACAGUUUUCUUCUUUCUUGAAUCCGGGUAAAAUUAGGAGUUUAUUAUAAAGCAGUAUCAGCGUGGGAAAUUUUCCAUGGAAAUGACAUAAAACUGCAUAUUUUUUGUCAAAGCAAAGAUUAGGUGUUUGAGAAAGCAAAUCAUAAGCAUUUUAUUAGUAUAAGAAGUAUUUAUUGCAAGGAUAAUAUGACGUUAUUCAACUCUUUUUUUUAUUUUUUAUCUUAUUUUUCCAUAAGUUAUUGGGGUACAGGUGGUAGUUGGUUACAUGAGUAAGUGCUUUAGCGGUGAUUUGUAAGAUUUUGGUGCACUUAUCACUAGAGCAGAAUACACUGCACCAUAUUUGUAGUCUUAUCCCUCACUCCUCUCCCACUCUUCCCCCCAAGUCCCCAAAGUCCACUGUAGCAUGCUUAUGUCUUUGUGUCCUCAUAGCUUAGUUCUCACAUAUCGGUGAGAACACACAACGUUUGGUUUCCCAUUCCUGGGUUACUUCACUUAGAAUAAUAGUCUCCAGUCUCAUCCAGGUCACUGCAAAUGCUGUUAAUUCAUUCCUUUUUAUGGCUGAGUAGUAUUCCAUCAUAUAUAUAUAUAUACACACACACACACACACACACACGCACACACACACACAUAUACACACACACACACAUAUAUACACACACACAUAUAUAUAUAUCUCACAGUUUCUUUAUCCACUCGUUGAUUGAUGGGCAUUUGGGUUGGUUCCAUGAUUUUGCAAUUGUGAAUUGUGCUGCUGUAAACACGCGUGUUCUUUAAGGAAUAUUCACACUGUUUUCCAUAGUGGCUGUACUAGUUUACGUUCCCACCAGCAGUGUAGAAAUGUUCCAGUCAAUUCUUAAUGACACAUUAAAACAGAGCACUAAAGUUAUUUAGUCUGCAAUAGUGUCAAGUAAAAUGCCAUUUAGUGGGGUCUAUGAAAGACUGGAAUUGCUUCACAUUUUAAGUGCCUAGUGACUAUUUUCCUCUUUUAGACAGUGUUCUUUGCAGUUAUACCAUGUACAGGAUAGCAGAACAUCUGAGAUUUUUAAGAAUUUUGUUCCCAUCUUACCCCUACCUUUAAUUUUAGGAAUAUAUUGUAGGAGUCUCUCAAACAGAAAACAUAAUUUGCAUUAUAUUUAUAGAAGAAGGAGGAAAUCCUCAAUUAGGAGCCAAACUAUGUGAUACCAACAAGAUAAUGAUGUCUCUUGUAUCAAUAUUUAUUACAUGUUGAAAUUUAUUUUAAAAAUCUUCAAAGUGUUUUAAAAAAUAAUUGCUGCUGCCCAGUGGAGUUCGUAACUGCAGCAUUAUUUAGCCUUUAUGGGAAUCAGAGAAAAUUUACAUUUUUCCUGAGUAGUUUCUUAUAUACAAUUCCACAAAGCGGAAUGGGAAGCUAUUUUAUCCUGAGUCAUUUUCCAAGCUCAGAAGCAUAAUGAAGGGUGUCAAACAAUGGAGAUUCGCCACUUGUUGAUAAGGUCAAGGCACAUGGCAUUUUGUAGCACAGCAGCAAUCAACCACCUCAUGCUGGAAUGUUGCCUGCUCCCCCUCACUAGGAAGGGGAGACUCACCCCAGCAGGCCAAUCAACCUCUGAGGCUUAUUCUUCUGGGAGGACCCUGCAGGGACAUUCCACAGGCAGCUCCUCAUGCAGGACUUGUUCCAGAUUGAAAUAGCUUCCAUGUGAGCUUUUCCUAGCUUUCAGAAAAUGUUUAUCCUCAAACUUAGUACACUCAUUUGUUCCAAGGUGGGCCCACUGGAACAACCAGAGUUUGAUAUAAGUCUCUGGAAACACAUCUAUACAUAUAGUCUUUUCUACUUUACUGUACCGGGGGAAGGUACUGAUCUGGGAAAUAAAGAAGAAAUAGGAAAUAAAGAGACAGGACUGUCCGGUGGACUUGGGUACAUUUGGCACCCUAAAAAUGGGGGGAAAACAAGGUGCCUGUGUUAGUUCUGGAUUCCAUGUUGUUGAGAGUCACCUUUGCAACAAUUUUGUAACUCAUACAGUGUGUGUAUGGGAAUAAAGUUGUACAUGUACAAUGGGGGUAUACCUUAGGAAGACUAUCAGUGUUUCUAAAAACAUUACAGAAGGCAAAUGUUAUUUAUAAUCAAAUUACCCUUGAAAACACUACAGUAACUCUGUUAGUUAAUGAUAUUCUAUUGGCGUUAAUUAAUUAUUCAAUUUAUUUUUCAAAUGUGGUGAAAAAAUCAUCACCAGAUAGUUGUCCAACCUUUUUUUUUCGGUAGUGGCAGAAAAAUCCUUAAUAUCAAAUGAUACUACUUUUUUUCUUGUUUCAGCAACUCACGUUGGCUAUUUUAGGUUCACUUGCAUCCAUUUCUGUUUAAGUGACACAACAGUGGUUGCCAAGUAUAUAUUGUUGAGUAUUUAUAUAUUAAAUCUACAUUUAUUAAUACUAUGGACCCUUAGCAUUUGUAAAUCAUUUUUAUUGAUUUCAACUAUUAUUUGCCAACCCCAUGGAGUCACAACCCACGCUGACAUAAUUCUGCUGAGGCACCUCUUUUAAACACAGGGGACGUAGCACUUUCAAAUGAGUUCAGCCCAACCCAGUGCUUGCUCUUAUUUGUCACUGAUUACCAGGUAGCGCGGAGUACAAGAACUUGGGGACACUGAGAGUCUCCAGUCAUAAACUAUGCAAAUGUCAAGGGUCAUGUGUGUGCCCACAAUGAGCAUCGCUAAGAUACAUUUUAAACAACUUCCAUUUAAAUAUUAUUAAAAUGCCAAUUGUAUUCAUGUGGUUUCUACCAUGAAAUGAUGUUAAUCGGGAACAUUUUAAAAAUAAACCAAGACGAGCUUCAUCCAGUUUCUACAUAUCAUACAGCAACCAUUUGAGCCAGAAAAAGAUUAACUGCAGCAUCUUUAUAACAUAUUGGCAUCAUAUAUCUAAUUAGUUUUUUCCUUCCCUUAUUUCUUAGAAAAUCAAUAGACAAAAAGCGAGUCCUCUCAAAAGAAUGGCUGUAAAUUCCAAAGGUGCAAUCAGUGGAGAAAGGGGUGAGAAACUUCAUUCGCAAUCUGCAACCCCAUGGAAUACAGUUAGACAUUUUCAGGCUAUGGGAAGAUGUUCCUGACAAUGGAGGGGAGCUUGUGUACUUUUUCCUCUGUCCCUCUUGUUUAUUUUUUCUGGUUCACCUAGUAGUAAGUCAUUUUUCUUUCACAGCAUCUGCCAUGCCAUCUGUCUCUGCUACAAUAUCUGGCAACGAUGGCAUGUUUUCCAGUCCUAGAAAAAAAUCAGCCCCACAUCCCAUUUCCUCCUUCUUAUGGGUCUGUGUUCCUCCCAGUAGAGUCACUGACAGUUCUUUAUGCUCUAUGAAGCUCAUAUCCCUAAUUCUGUCACUUCCACAAAUCCCUAACCUGUAUUUCAAAAUCUUCUCUCGAGCUCAUUAGACAAGAAAAAGUUCAGGCAAUAGAGUCAGUCUGGACAUGGAUGGACACAGAGCAUUUGUGUGUCCAAGGAGCCAUAUGAGGAGUUUUUUGGGUUUUUUUGUUUGUUUCUUUUGACUUUCUGUCAUUCCCAAACACCAGGCUAAUAUCUCUACCUAUACUCUUCUCACUGCUCCAGGAAGAACAGAUUGAGCCUAACUGUGGUCAUGAAAGGAAGGUAUAAGCCUGUACCACUUGUAGACAACAGCAAGAAGAGGGGACACACUAACUUUUCGAUCUGAAAAUAUGAUUUUUAAAUUAAAUUAAAUUUUAGUUAGUUUUUUAUUUUAAAAACACUUGGAUUUGAGUCCUUACUUUUCAUAUAGAGCUUGUUGCCAAGACUGAUUAUUCUUACAGAAUUCCUGAGUCAUUAAAUAUUAUUUCCAUGCUGAUAACGGUUCCAGUUAUUAAUUUUUUCCUGCCAGCAGAUCAGCACAGACAUAAAGCAGCCCAGAUGUCUCAAUUUCAAAUAAGAGAAGCAAGACCAAAGUUAGCUUCACUUAUUCCCAUAGUAUCAUCUUGUCAAAUAACCCAUUCCAUAAGUAUUUACUUCUUUCUAAGCCAUCUUUUUUAGUGUUGUCAUGUGAAAGCAGGCAUCUAUGGAUAUUCAGGGAUUCAGGAUAUCCAAUGACAACUUAGAAAAUGCCAGAAAGCAAAAAACAUUGCAGUAUCCCAAAUUUUCUACAUUUUGACAGUUCCAAAAUACUGGACCUAGAUAUUUAACUUCCAAAGUAAAAAGUUUUCAAAACCAAAAUUAACCACCUAAAACCUAGAAACAUCAUUUAACCACAGUAGAUCAGGCCUUCUGCCUCUAUCUUUUAUUAUCUUCCCUGAAAGUUACCUUCAAGCCAUUCGAAAAAACAUGAUAUAGAAGGAAGAAAUCUUCUGCAAAUAUUAUCAGGGAGCUGUCCAAUAGAAAUAUAAUGCAAGCCACAUAUAUAUAAUUUAAAUUUUCUAUUAGCUACAUCAUUAAAAAAGUAAAAAGAGAGAGGAACAACACAUAUCGGGGCCCGUUGUGGGGUGGGGGGCAAGGGGAGAGAGAGCAUUAGGAUAAAUACCUAAUUCAUGCAGGGUAUAAAGCCUAGAUGACGGGUUGAUGGGUGCAGCCAACCACCAUGGCACAUGUAUACCUAUGUAACAAACUUGCACGUCCUGCACAUGUAUUUCUGAACUUAAAGUAAAAAAAAAAAAGUAAAAAGAAACAGGUGAGGUUAGUUAUUAUAUUUUAUUUAAUGUGAUAUAUCAAAACUUACCACUUCAGCAUGAUCCAUUAGUAUCCAAAAGUUACUAAUGGCAUAUAUUACAUUCUUUUUUUUCCCUACUAAGUCUUUGAAAUCAGUUGUGUACACCCUAAUUUGGAGCAACACAUUUCAGCUGCUCAGUAGACAAUUUUAAUUAGGAUCAGCCACAUUUCAAGUGCUCAAUAGCCACAUGUGGCUAGUAGCUACUGUACUUGACCACGCAGGCUUAUAAACCAUAUUCCCAGUCUGACAGAGCCGCAGACACAUAGUAGGUGCUCAAUAAAUAUUUAUUGACUAGCUGGAUGAAUGACUGAGCAAGUGUUUGAGUGAUUGAAUGAAUAAAGCUCCAAAGUUAAAUAGCUCCAACUUCAUUUUCCUCUACUUGAAAACCCAUCUUGGUUUCCUAACCUCUAUAAACAUUCUAGUACCUGGUUCAACAUAUUUCAAGGAGAUGUUGACAGGUUGCUGCCAAACAGCCCCAGGACACUUACAUGCUGUUUCUCAUCUACAAUCACAGUAGCAUCCAGAUGCACUGCAUCUCUCUUUAGAAAUCUGAUUGAUAUCUAAAUGAGCAGAAAUGAAUAAAGGGACAAUUUGGCAAUACAGCUGCCCCCUGAGUAUUACUGUAUCAAUUAAGAUUAUUUAAUGCAUUUCAUUUAUUACCCUGGCCAGGACGUUCCCAAGGCCUCUGGUGUACAUCAGAUCAAUUUAACCCCCUGGUUUGAAAGCCCGGGACAGUUGAGUUUUCAAGAAAUUAAUUUGGAGAAAAUGAUUUUCAUAUCCAAGAAGAUGAGCCAAACCCAGCCAAGCUUGUUGCAAAAAAAAAAAAAAAAAAGUGUUUCAAUUUUAAAAAGCAGUUUUGUUUCCAUUUUAACUGCAAAUUCACCAAAAAUUUUCCUGAUACUUUAGGCCUAUUUAGCUGAUGUUUUGUCCUGUACAGACCAAAAAAAUUGUGUCAUAAAAAGACAAAUUUAUUUCAUCCGUCCUAAGAAAUGACAAUGGGGGACAGUAGGGUUCACUUCAGGUUCUUUCCAUCUCAAGUUCGUCUGUUUAGAAAAUCUCAUGUUUCUGUUCAUAGUGGACCUCCUCAUUGGAACAAUAUUUCUGCAGAGUGGACUAGGGCAUUAGACAGACACAACUUCAAAUUCUGGCUUUGCUACCUAUCAGACUGUACACUUGGGAAAAGCUACUAUCCUCACAGAGGCUCACUUUCCUCACCUGAAAACAGAGGAAACAUAAAGCACCAUCUGAAUGAGUUAACAAUGUGGUUACAGCACCUCACUCACAGCUGGGGCAAACAAACGUAAGCUCCAUUUCUAGAAUGCCCUAGGUAAGGCAUGUAAAACUCUCCUUUCUCUGGAUCUCUUCUCAGAGGUAAUCAUGGGAGAAGUCCAAGGCCCUGAAAUUAUAAUAUGAUGAAAAUCUAAUGGAGAUAGCCAAGCUGCAGGGCUGCACAGGAUCUGUGAUGAAGUCAUGUAAGAUUCAAGCCAUGGAGUUGGCAGUGUAAUUUUCUUAUAGCCCUUUUUUUCCUCCUAAAAUUUUGCUCUGAAACUCUUUAUGCCCUUUAAGCUGAUUUAAUCAUAAAUUUUCCAGGGUUAAUCUAUUCAGCCUGAAAGGUGAUCUUGUGCCUGUGACUUUAUUUUCAAAGAUGUCUCUAGAAAAAAAAAACAACUCAAUAAUAGGAUUAACUCAUUCAUUCAGUUGAUAUUCACUGAAUACUUACUAUUUAAGCACUGUUUUGGGCACUUGGAGAAGCAGAAGUUAAUAAACAAAAAUCCUAUCCUUAGAAAAAUCACAUUCUUGUUGGGGAGACAGACAAAAAGUUAGUAAGAAAGUUACAUUAGAUGGUGAUAAUAGAAUGGAGAAACAAACUAAUCAUGGGAGGGGGCUAGGAAGUUAUGGGGGUAGAUUUUAGUUAGGAUGACCUAAUAGGAGGAAAUGGUGGGCAGUGGGGAGGGGGUUUGGAAAAUAGCUUGGACUCCUCCAAAAUAGCAAAGGUAUGGCAUUAAGAGUCAGACCUCAAUUCAAAUCCUCUUUCUGUUACGAGCCAAUUGAUCUUAGGCAAGUUAUUGAACUUCUCUUGUCCCUGGUUUUCUUAUCUGUAGAACGUAGGUAAUAAUAUCUGCUCUAUAGGGUUAUUGUGAGGAUUAUUUGAGAUAAUAUACACAAAAUGCUUAGGAUGUUGCCUAGUAACUACUCGAAAUUUAGAGCUACCAUUUUUGUUAUUAUUACUGUUUGUAUAGUACUGCUGUAAUUUUUUUAUGCAGGAAAUUACCUUGAUGCAAUUGUAGUCUCCAGGUCUACUACCAGGUUAUCCUAGAGGUCUCAAAGAAGAAGGCUAACACAACAAAUUAAGAUGCAUGAGUCACAUGGUUUAUCAAAUCAAUUAAAACACAUUAUGAGAAGAAAGAGGGGAAGAGAUAGGGACAGUUAAAAUAAUUACACUAGAAUUCACGCAGGAGAAAGAACCCAGCUACUUAAAUCUUGGGACACACAGUGCUCAUGUGACCUGUUCUCUCUAUCUACCACAUUGACCUUCUCCGUGGUGUGAUUAUAUAGGUCAAAUCUGAGGUUUCAGCAAGGGGCUCAGCAAGGAAAAGAUGCCCGGGUCAGUAGUAUACUUGGAAAGACACAGGGACAAGCCCACCUGGCCAUGACCUGUAGCUCAUCAUUUGGCCUGAUGAACAGCUAAGGACUAUUUGCAUUCCUUGCACAGAGGAUUUCUGUGGCUAGAAUGGGGGUCACCAAUGGGUGGCUGACUGAAGACUUAAGUUCUCAUAUUUUAUGUAUUUAUAUUUAGUAUAUUUCAAAUGUUUGAUGUCGUAUGCAUAUGGAUAUGUUGUCAAUAUCACCUCUUUCCAUUCCUCCCUCCUAUCUGUGUUCAGCAUGCACAUUCUCUACUUUGUUGAUGGCCACUAUGACUCAGGGGUUACUAAUCCACUUAGUUUUACCAUGCUCAUCAUAUAAAUUCUGCCUAUGUCUCACAAGCUACUUGCAUCUCCACCCAGUUUCAUUUAUCCUCUUUCUUUGUUUCACUUUCUUUCUUGAGCAGAACUGAAUAAUCUUAAGUCAUACAGCAAAGGCACAUUACAGAGUUCACCACUCUCAGUUGUUGACAUGUUGCCUCAGGUCCGGCAAAUCUUCCAGGCCUGUUGAAAAAUUUCCAGCAUUAACAAGAGGCCCACAAAGUUCUGACUGUGGAUCAUUCUGAUAUGCAUCUAUAAGAACAGAGCCCCUGGUUAACAAAUGAUCUUUUCCAACUGGGUUCCAUAGAAAGAACAAGAGCUUUAGAGAAAUUACCUUUACUAGAACUACUGAGAAGUUAACAAUUGCCAAGGCUGCAGAAAAUAUGUGAAGAGCUGGCUUUAAAGAAAACUAUACUCCAGAAAAACAAUUGUACUCAUCUGGUGUUGUAUUUUCCGCUUUCUUUGGAAAUCAGUGAUUCCCAACCUUAUUCCAUAAAGUCCUGGUUUGAAGGGAAGAUUCUAAAGAAGGAUAUGCUUAUAUGCUAUGCAGUUUACUUCCUCUAUUUUCUCUCCUCCCUCCCCCACCUUUUUUUUCUUUCAUGACAUCUUUACUCAACAGCGAAGGCAGAAGAGAUUCAAUCUGUAUCAUUCAGUAAGUUAAAAAAGGAAAAACAAGGUGGGCCAAAUGUUUGGGAGACUAUUGUACCUUCUCACAACAAGUCUGUGGACUUCACCAAGCUCCAAAAGGAUGCUUUUUUCUUCUUCUUCUUUUUCCCUUAAGUUGUUUUUAGUUAAGAAAAAAGAGAGAGAGAGAGGGAGAACAGAGAGUGCUUCUGCUCACCCCAGCUGUCAGGUGAAAAACAGAGCUGCUUAGUAUUCUGGGGCUGUGGGUUUAUGACUCAUGUGCACUUCCUUCUGUGAGUUGUCAUUUCUCUGAGAGAUAUUUGGAGUUGUGACAAAAUUUAACUCCAUAUUCUGAGGGGAUGUUGACUGGAUCUCAGGAGAAUUCAUUUCUGUAAGUUCCUCGAUCUGCUGCAGCAGAUCUGCAGUGACAUGCAGAGGACUUGGAGACUAACAUGACUUAGCAGCAACACACUCUGAGGGUUUACUGGCAUGCUGAUUGAAUGCAGUGAGCAGAGCCACCUGUGUCAGGGUAAUCGAAAAUUCUCAGACAGCCGGGGAUAAACAAAUACCCUCGAGUCUCUCUCUUACUUUCUGUACAAAAGGAAGUAUUAAUAAUGAGAGUAAGUGGUUUUGUUAACCCCCCUCCUGAAUAUUUAAUAUGUGUCCUAAAAAAAUAUGAGGUCUGCAAUCAGAAGGUGAGGGCGUUAGUCUUAGGUAUAUAAACUUGGCUGAGUUGCUCAGACCUUCAGCUUCUCAGUUUUUCAUUUGUAAAAUGGGAAGAAUAAAAAUAUUCUAGCUAUUUCCAAGAUUGUUGUGAAGACAAAAUGAGAUAAGUGGAAACAUGUUAUAAAUUGUAAUUGUCCUGCACAAAUAUUUUGAGGUUGUUGUUGUUACAUAUGUUUACACUUUUAGGAAUAUAUAAACCUUGGAAGAUGUAAUAAUCAAAGUUUCAGCCAGACACCAAGAAACAAUUGAAAUGACAUUUUAGAGUGAGAUGCCAGUUCUCCAUUUGUACUUUCAAAUGAAGUGUGCAAGAGCUUGUUCCAUAGCUCUUUCUUCCCCCAACUUUUUAUUUUGAGAAAUUAAAAACUUAUAGAAAUGGUGAAAGAAUAAACACCCAAUACUCUUCACCUACAUUUACCAAAUUGUGCCACAUUUUGCCUUUGUUUUUCCCUCUCUUGUUCUUUGCCAUUGUGACAUUUCAUUCAUAAAUAUUUUCUCCAGUAUCUCCUGAGAAUAAGGCAUUCUUCUAUAUGACCAUAACACAAUCAUCAUACUCAAGAAUAUUCAAGCCAUAUUCAAAUUUUCUAAAAUGUCCUUUAUAGGAUUUAUUUGUUUUGCUUUUUUGGGGGGGGCAUGAAUCCUGCAGUACAUUUAAUUGUCAUGACUGUUAAAUUUUUUUAUUUUAUUCUAUUUUAGAUUCGGGGGUACAUGUGCAGGUUUGUUACAUGGGUAUAUUACAUAAUGCUGAGCUUUGGGCUUCUAGUGAACUGAUCACCCAAAUAGUGAACAUUGUACCCAAUAGGGAGUUUCUUAAGACUCACCACCCUGCCACCCUCCCCUCUUUUGGAGUCCCCAUUGUCUAGUAUUUCCAUCUUCAUGUCCUUGUGUAGCCCUUGUUUAGUUCCCCCUUACAAGUGAGAACAUGACGUAUUUGAUUUUCUGAUUCUAUUUCACUUAGAAUAAUAGCCUCCAGCUCCGCCCAUGUUGCUGCAAAGGACAUGAUUUCAUUCUUUUUUCUGUCUGCAUACUAUUCCAUAGUAUUUUCCACACUGUUUUCCGAGGGCCCAGGAGGGUUGCUGCAUCCCAUUGCUGGUCCUGUUCAGGUUGAUCACUCGAUUCAAGUGAUGUCUGCCAGGUUUCUCCCCUGUGACAGUACCUCUUUAACUUUAUAACUAAUAAAUAACCUAGAAUGUGAUUAUUUGAGACUAUGUGAAUAGCCUGUCCCCCACAACCUUGUUUUAGCACCCACCAAGGAUCCCUGCCUGUGUCCGCUUUUAUAAGGAGGGCUGUGAGACGGUGCUUUCCUGAUUCCAUCAGCUCCUCUUUCUUUAGGAGUUGGUUUUCUUCUACAAAGAGAAGCUUUCCCUUCUGCUCUUACCCUACUCUCUGUUCAGUGACUCUGGAGCUCCUCACUGGCUUCAAAAGUAUAAAAGUUGAGAGAGGGGAGUAAAGGGGGUCUAGUGAGAAGGGCACGUAUGAAGAAAACUGUGCUGUGAGCUCCAUCCACCCCAGCAUGGGAGAAGGCUGCCUCUUCAUUGCCACCCUGGUUGGGAUGGGGGUUUGAAGGCCAUUCAGAUGGUUUAAAACAUUACCCCCAUGACUGGGGAGCAUAGUGGCCUAGGAGCUGAUGCAUGCCUGGAAAAUCCAGGGGUAAAGAGGUGGGCUGACUAUCUGUCUUGGUGGCACCACUGGGGGAGUGCUGACCUCCUGGGACUGGUAGGGAAGGUAGUUACAAAUGUCUCCUGUGUGGGGUCUUCUUGAGUCCUGCCCUUCAGGGCCUCCUGGAGGAUGAAGGCUGGAGGACAGGGAUUUGAGGGAGAAAAUAGAGAAACAGAGAAACCAAACAUACCUGACACUCUUGUAGUCUUCUAGCCUAAACAGGUCCCAGCUUGGGCAGAGGAAAAGAGUUUGAGUUUGAAGUUUGAUUGAGAUUGUUGGAGGAUGUGCUUAUGACUUAAAAUGACUUUAGGUCUCUGUAUUACCAUAGAAUGAGCAGAAAAGAUGUGGGACCAGUCUGAGUUUUCAUCAAGGCCAAAGGAUACUUGCUCUACUGAAUGUUAAGGACCAGUAGGAGAUUUAAAAAAAUUAAGCUGAAGGAUUACAUUAUCAUUAGUUAUGCUUGUUACACGUUUAAAUACCUAAGUUUAAAUCUGACUUAAAUUACAUGCACAUGCCAAAAAAAUUUAACUCUUAGUUUCAGAAACAAAUUUGUUUACUUUAUAUGAAAAUACCAUUAAGUCCAAUAUAACUGGAAGUUUAGGAAAACCUUAUGUGCUUAAGAUUCGAGUCUCCAUAAAUUACAGAAUAAAGCACUUGGCCCCCUGUAUAAAAUUCAUACAUUAUACAAAGACAUCCCUCAUACUCCAGCACUACUUCACCCCACAUACCCUCCUUGGGAAUCUGAAAACUUUUGAGGUGUCACUUCAACUUUGGGAAGUAAUUAUUUGUUAAUGUUCAAAUAGUGGAAAAUAUUAUAUGCCACAAAAGCCUCAACCUCUGCAGUUUGGAAUUUACCCAUCAUUUCUAAAUGUAUCCCCAUGUUAAGUUUUAUGUAUUUGUUUUAAAUUCAAAAGGGAAAGCGUGUGUUGUGUCUAGCUCCAGUGAAGCCAAUCAUACAAAAUUGCUGAUAAUUAAAUAAGAUACUUUUAGACUUAAAAUUUUGACAAUCCAAAUAUAGUCAGCUCAGAAUUUGCUUAUUCAAGAAAACCAUUUUGUUUGUUUUUAAGGGCCAGUGGAUGGAACAGUUUGUACAGGGAAGCAGUAGGAAGGGAAAGAAAGCUUAGUGUUAACCAAUAUUCUUCUGUAUUAAGGGCAAAAAGGAAAGCAUUGUAUCAUCGCCUUUGAAACUAGAAGCAAGUUUGGUAAUUAAACAAACCCAAUAACCACUUUAAAAUGAAUGUUUUUAUCUAAUGAGAUAGGAGAUAAACCCAUCUGACAAGAGAAUUCACAUAAAACUUAACAAAAAGCCAAAAAAGGGAGAUAAAAAAAAAAUAAAAAAUGGGUAAGAGGAAAGAAUGAAAUUUUGUUUCUCUCAUCCCUACUCUCUUCCUGAGCAGAGAUCAAAUGUUGCAAGACCCUGUCUCAAAAACCCUACGUAAUGCAUUUUAAAUGUCACCAUAUAGUACUCAGAUGACCCACAGAAGAACAUGACAUAGUAUAAACACUCAGGUGCAAAACCUGGCCUUGUGCAUUUAUUCAUAUCCAACUAAUAUUUAUUGAGUGUCUACUGUAUACCACAGCAUACAUAGGAUUUAUUAGAGAACAACAUAGACAAAGAUCCCAGCCCCUGUUGGGCACAUUCUUUCUGGCAGGAGAGAUAAGAAACAAUAAUAUAACAAAAAGUUAAAUUGUAUAGAAUAUUAGAUGUUGAUGGGUGCUAUAAAAAAAAAAAAAAGAAAAACUAAAGCAGGGAAAUUAGAAUGGGAAUGCUUAGGAAGUUGGAGUUGGCCAUUGAGAAGGUAGGGUUUGAGCAAGGACUUGAAGAAGUCAGGUGAAUAGCCAUAAGAGAGAUAAGGAGACUACUUCUGGCUGUAGAAACAGUGCAAAGGCCCUGAGAUGGGAGCCUUCUGUCAUGUUUGAGGAACGUCAAGGACAUAGAUGUGGCUGCAGCAGAGUAAGGAAGGGGGAAGGUAGAAGGAGACGAGUUUAGAGAAAUAAGUGAGGCCAGAUCUUUGGGCUCUCUGAAUUUUUGACAAAAAAGUGACGUGACUUGACUUACAUUUCAAAAGGAUACCUCCUCCUUGGAUUGAGAAUACGUUAUAGGGGCAGCCUUCUCAAUAGCCAACUCCAGAGUCCUAAGCAUUCCCUCCUUGGAUUGAGAAUACAUUAUAGGGGCAAAUGUAGGAGCAGGGAGAUAUGUUAAAAAAUGGUUAUAGCAAUCUAGAUGAGAGAAUAGGGUGCAGAUGAGGGCACUAGCCGUGGACUGUAAUGUGGUUCAGUUUGGAUAAAUAAUGAAGUUAGAGGCAACGGAAGUUCCUGGUGAAUUAGAUAUGAGCGUGACUGAAAGAAAAGAGUGAAGAAUGACUCCAAGGUUUUAGGCCUGAGUCACCAAAAGGAUGGAGUUGCCAUCAGUUGAUAUGGGAUUCAUAGCUGAUAUGGAACCAGCUGUGGGGAAGCUCAGGGGUUUGAGUUUAGUCAUCUUGAGUUUGAAAUGUUUAUUAGGUGGCCAAGUGAAGAUGCUGAGUAGGGAGUUAGACACCAAAGCUGAAACUCCAUCUUGGGAUGAAGGCAUAAAUUUGGGAGCUGUCUGCAUGCGAAUGGUAUUUCAACCCUUGAGAAUUGAUGAAAUCACACAAGUAGUAAAAGCAGAAAAAAAAGAAGAUAUAGAAAGAAAGGACUGAGGACUGAGCUCUGGGACUCUCCAGUGUUAGGAGGUUGAGAGGAUGGGGAGAAGCGUGUAAUGUUCAAGAAAGAAAUAAAGAAAUCACAUCAAAGAGGAAGAAGGGAUCAACUAUAUCAAAUGUUACCGAUAGGUCAAGUAAGAUGAAGACGGGAUCAGCUAUAUCAAAUGUUACUGAUAGGUCAAGUAAGAUGAAGACUGAACAUUGUCUAUUGGUGUUAACAAUGUGGAAAUCUUUAACAACAUUGACAAGAGAGUUCUGGUGAAGUAAGAAGGGAGUGGGUGAGUAAAAGCCACUUAGCCUCUGACUCACAGUUUCCUAAUUUGGAAAAAAGUAAGGAAACAUCUGGAAUUAGCAGGACAAAGUAAAAAUGCUUCUACCCUUUCCUUUUAAAAAAUAAAAAGCUACCCAAUACACAACACAGAGACAAAGAAACAGAAAUAGAAACUUCAUUUCUCAUGAAAGUGUCAGUGAACUGAAAACCUAGACCAAUAUGUAUGAAAAUGGAAAAGGGAUGAGGAUUAUAAAUGACUUAGCAGAACUGAGGAAAGAUUUUUUUUAAGUGCCUGCAGAUGAGUAACAACUUAACAUGUACCACACAACCUCAGGAUGGUUCAUCUAUUAGAGAAUCCAAUGUCACGGAAGAUGGGGGUGAGGCAGGGACCAGGAACAAGGUAGUUCUUUAAAAGAGGAUACAGAGCUACUAAAGCUCAUGUCCCCAGGUCUGCAGUCAGUGUCCUGCCUUUCUCCUCCAAUGAAGGAAGAGGAGUUUUAUUAACUGGAGACAUUGAGUUGACAGGCUCUAAGCUGAGAGAUAUCAGGCACAGAGCAAGGUGGAGCCAGGCUGCAAAUAAAAAGACUAUGAGACUUGAGACCCCAGACCCCUUCUCUCACCCAUGUCCAGGUCACCAGCAGCCAGGUCACACCCUCCCCAUGCAGAAGACAGAGUAUCUCCUAGGAGACAAUUAACUGUCCCAGGAAAAAUUCUAACAGAUAUUGACAUUGUUGUGGAAGAAAACCCUAUUGAAAAUUACAGCAUGAAUGGCACUAGUGGACAAACACCGUUCAAGCACAAUUUUAGUGCUUUAUUCUUAAAUGUGAACUGAAACCCAAGGAUCAUCUGACAUUCAAAGAAAGUCUCUAACAGGAAAAGAAGCUCAAAUAAAUAGAAAAAAGAAAACAGAGUAAUGCAGAGAGAUACAGAAAUGUUCAAAGAAACUAUAAUAUACUUGGUGAUAUAAGAGAAGGUACUACAUCAAUAGAACAGAAACGAGAUGGAAAAGAGCAAGAACAACAUAGAACUAGAAAAAGAUUUUACAUAUUUAAAAUACAAUGGCUAAUUUUUUAAAGUCAAUUAGAAUGCUGGACAUUAAAGUUGAGAAAAUAUUCCAGAAAGUAAAAGAGAAAAAGGAAUGGACAAUAGGAGAGAAAAGAUAAGAAAAUAAGGUUCUGUCCACGAGUCCAACAUCUUUUCAACUGAAGGAUAUCUUGAGAGAGAACAGAUAAAAUGGAGGAGGGGGAGUUAUCGCAAAGCAAUACAAGAAAAUUUCCAGAUCGGAAGAACACAAGUCUCCAGAUGGAAAGUGCCCACUCAGUACCCAAUACAGUGAAUAGAGAUUGACGCAAAGAAACAUUAUCAUGAGAUUUCACAACUGAAAAGAGAAAGAAAAGCAUCCUAAUACAUUUCAGAGAUUUAAUUGAAUACACACAUGAAGGAUCCAGAAAAAAGAUUGCUGGAUUCUCAACAGCAACAUGGGGAACCAAAACACCAUGAAGCAGGCCUUCAAAAUUCUAAGCAAAAAGAUGAUGGGCAAACUACAAACCAAGGGUGAAGAAGUAAUGUCAUUUUGACUUUCCUGUCUCUCAAACACAAUUUCUCCACAAGCUGCUGGAAAAUAUGUUCCACCAACACAUAAAGAUAAAGCCACAAAGUGGAAGCCAUGGGAUCCAAUUCAUUAAAGGGAGGAGAAGAAUUUUCCAGAUAAUGGGAAGGAAAACGCCAAGAGGACAGCCAUGCAGCAGGCACAGAAAGUGACCAGCAGAGACUGCAGCAGGACGAUGGAGGGCUCUAGAAGAAAUGUUGCCAGGAAAACAAAAAGGAACUGAGUUUCUUAUCAGCUUGACCAUGUGGAAAACUGUACUGAGAGAUAUUUGGAGCUCGGCUGUAGCUCCAAAUCAAACUAAAUUAAUAAAGCAAUUGUUUAAUGAAAGGUAACAUGAAAAUAUAUGGGAGAAAGGAAAUACAAUCAUUAUAGAUGACUUUGCUCAGCCAUGGAUAUUAAAUACUUAGUCAUAAAAAUGAAAACACAGUGAAUUAUACUUACAUUUGUGAGAUAAACUUAACUUGCUUAUGAUGUAUUAUUUUAUCAUUUUAAAUAUCAUACUAUAUCUGGUAAGCUAAUAUUUAAUUUAGGACUUUUAUGCCUAUAUUCAUAAAAAAAAUUAGCCUGUAAUUUAUUUUCUUAUAUUGCCUUUAUUUGGCUUUGGAGGUCUUUUUACUCCUCUUAUAGGGCCACAGGACUCUAUAAAUAAUGAAUAUUUAAUACACGCUAGCUAUCUAAUAUUAUUCCUUGAUGAAAAAAUAGGAGGUGAUAAAAUUAGGAAACAAUAAAAAGAACAGAACCAGAUAGAGAACUCUAAGUGUCCUGAUUAGCACUGCAUAGUAUCAGAGAAAUUAUUCGAUUCUGGAAUGUAAUUUGGCUAAAUUUAAUUACACCAUCCUCUUUUAAAACAUCAAGACACAGACAAGAAUGUAAGUCUUUUGUUUCAGGUCUCAUAGCUAAUUAUUGGAGGAACUAGAACUAGAAUCCAAUUAUCCAGAAUUCUGACUCCUAGCCCUAGUGCUCCUAUAAAAAUGUAUAUUAAUAGAUACUAACUAUGUCACCUCUAAUUUGGUUGGUGAUAGGUACAUUCCAUUUCAAAAAAUAAAAGUGAAUUGAGCGU